UGCGGUGGCAUCGGUUCUUCUCCUUAUUUUGACCCACACUGGCAUGCCACCUGAAGUCCCGAUAACAGCCUGAUUUCUCACUAAACACUCCAUCGAACCAUUUCAUUAUUUGUCUCUCCUAUUUUCAGCACUUUCCUUUUGCUUUCACAAAGCUUAAGGGAGAAUCAGCUAUGACAGAGAAAUUCCUUUUCCUUUAUCUUUCCCUCCUUCCCAUGCCCCUACUCUCACAGGCACAGUGGAAUGAAAAUUCCCUUGUCAGUUUUUCCAAAAUAAUUGCUUCGGGAAACCAUCUAAGCAACUGUUGGAUCUGCCACAACUUCAUCACCAGGUCCUCAUCUUACCAAUAUAUUUUGGUAAGAAAUUUUUCUUUAAACCUAACAUUUGGUUCAGGAAUCCCUGAAGGCCAACAUAAAUCUGUUCCGCUCCAGGUUUCGCUUGCUAACUCAGCGCACCAAGUCCCCUGCCUGGAUCUCACUCCACCUUUCAAUCAAAGCUCUAAAACUUCUUUCUAUUUCUACAACUGCUCUUCUCUAAACCAAACCUGUUGUCCAUGCCCUGAAGGACACUGUGACAGGAAGAACACCUCUGAGGAGGGAUUCCCCAGUCCCACCAUCCAUCCCAUGAGCUUCUCCCCAGCAGGCUGCCACCCUAACUUGACUCACUGGUGUCCAGCUAAACAAAUGAACGAUUAUCGAGACAAGUCACCCCAAAACCGCUGUGCAGCUUGGGAAGGAAAAGAGCUAAUCACAUGGAGGGUUCUAUAUUUGCUUCCCAAGGCACACACUGUCCCCACAUGGCCAAAAUCUACUGUUCCCCUGGGAGGGCCUCUAUCCCCUGCAUGCAAUCAAACUAUUCCAGCAGGGUGGAAAUCGCAGUUACACAAGUGGUUCGACAGCCACAUCCCCCGGUGGGCCUGUACCCCUCCUGGCUAUGUAUUUUUAUGUGGGCCACAAAAAAAUAAACUGCCCUUUGAUGGAAGUCCUAAGAUAACUUAUUCAACCCCCCCUGUGGCAAACCUCUACACUUGCAUUAAUAACAUCCAACAUACGGGAGAAUGUGCUGUGGGACUUUUGGGACCACGGGGGAUAGGUGUGACCAUUUAUAACACCACCCAACCCAGACAGAAAAGAGCUCUGGGUCUAAUACUGGCAGGGAUGGGUGCGGCCAUAGGAAUGAUCGCCCCAUGGGGAGGGUUCACUUAUCAUGAUGUCACCCUCAGAAAUCUCUCCAGACAAAUAGACAACAUAGCUAAGAGUACCAGAGAUAGCAUCUCUAAACUCAAGGCCUCCAUAGAUUCUCUAGCAAAUGUAGUCAUGAACAACAGAUUGGCCUUAGAUUACCUCUUAGCAGAGCAGGGUGGAGUCUGUGCAGUGAUCAGUAAAUCCUGUUGCAUUUAUGUCAAUAACAGUGGGGCGAUAGAGGAGGAUAUAAAAAAGAUCUAUGAUGAGGUUACGUGGCUCCAUAACUUUGGAAAAGGUGAUUCAGCAGGGUCCAUUUGGGAGGCUGUGAAGUCUGCCCUCCCCUCCCUCACAUGGUUUGUCCCUUUACUGGGACCAGCUGCACUUAAUAGCCUGCUUUCUCCUCUUUGGCCCUUGUCUCUAUAAUUCACUAAUUAAAUAUGUCUCUUCCAGGAUAUGGCAAUUUCACACAGAGCCCCUAAAAAUGGAAAGAGAUCAUCCAAUCUUCCUUGGAGGUCCCAGCACCUACAAGUACAUAUCUCCCUUGGAUGCCAGUGGGCAAAGAUUCUGCAACUACGGAGGGGCUCCUUCCCUGACAGAGAGCAAGAGAGGGAGACCCUGAUGACUUCUUCGUCCCACGUCAGCAGGAAGUAGUUACAGAAGACCCACGACGUCCUUAUGCCCAAAGCUUUUCAGGGUCUCCAACUCUUGAGGGGGAAUACUGUUAGGGUAGGCAGGUAGCCAGACAAGAGCAGGCAAGGAAGCCCCUGGGAAAGGAAUCUUUAGAAAUGCAGCCCGCUGAUGGCCUCCUUGGAAACGCUGCACGCUGAGUCAGCAAAAGGAGGAGCGUGGCUACACUGGCUACACCUGGCCUUGUGGCUGCAUUCCUCUGUUCCAGAAGGGAACUUAUCAAGGCCCAGCCAGAGGUUACCAAGGUAGGAGCUAUUCCCCACUAAGAAGCAUGUAUACUUCUCUAAUAAUUCACCCUAAUAUACCAUUUUGUUCAUUAAAAUAAUAAAAAAAAC